ACCACUCUUCUUCAAUUCUCCUAGAGCAUCUUUGGAAGCAUGAGGCCACGAUGCUGCAUCUUGGCUCUUGUCUGCUGGAUAACAGUCUUCCUCCUCCAGUGUUCAAAAGGAACUACAGACGCUCCUGUUGGCUCAGGACUGUGGCUGUGCCAGCCGACACCCAGGUGUGGGAACAAGAUCUACAACCCUUCAGAGCAGUGCUGUUAUGAUGAUGCCAUCUUAUCCUUAAAGGAGACCCGCCGCUGUGGCUCCACCUGCACCUUCUGGCCCUGCUUUGAGCUCUGCUGUCCCGAGUCUUUUGGCCCCCAGCAGAAGUUUCUUGUGAAGUUGAGGGUUCUGGGUAUGAAGUCUCAGUGUCACUUAUCUCCCAUCUCCCGGAGCUGUACCAGGAACAGGAGGCACGUCCUGUACCCAUAAAAACCCCAGGCUCCACUGGCAGACGGCAGACAAGGGGAGAAGAGACGAAGCAGCUGGACAUCGGAGACUACAGUUGAACUUCGGAGAGAAGCAACUUGACUUCAGAGGGAUGGCUCAAUGACAUAGCUUUGGAGAGGAGCCCAGCUGGGGAUGGCCAGACUUCAGGGGAAGAAUGCCUUCCUGCUUCAUCCCCUUUCCAGCUCCCCUUCCCGCUGAGAGCCACUUUCAUCGGCAAUAAAAUCCCCCACAUUUACCAUCUUCAA